CAUUUAAAUUCUGCAGCUCAGAGAUUCACACAGAAGUCUGGACACAAUUCAGAAGAGCCACCCAGAAGGAGACAACAAUGUCCCUGCUACCCGUGCCAUACACAGAGGCUGCCUCUUUGUCUACUGGUUCUACUGUGACAAUCAAAGGGCGACCACUUGCCUGUUUCUUGAAUGAACCAUAUCUGCAGGUGGAUUUCCACACUGAGAUGAAGGAGGAAUCAGACAUUGUCUUCCAUUUCCAAGUGUGCUUUGGUCGUCGUGUGGUCAUGAACAGCCGUGAGUAUGGGGCCUGGAAGCAGCAGGUGGAAUCCAAGAAUAUGCCCUUUCAGGAUGGCCAAGAAUUUGAACUGAGCAUCUCAGUGCUGCCAGAUAAGUACCAGGUAAUGGUCAAUGGCCAAUCCUCUUACACCUUUGACCAUAGAAUCAAGCCUGAGGCUGUGAAGAUGGUGCAAGUGUGGAGAGAUAUCUCCCUGACCAAAUUUAAUGUCAGCUAUUUAAAGAGAUAACCAGACUUCAUGUUGCCAAGGAAUCCCUGUCUCUACGUGAACUUGGGAUUCCAAAGCCAGCUAACAGCAUGAUCUUUUCUCACUUCAAUCCUUACUCCUGCUCAUUAAAACUUAAUCAAACUUCA